GAGUGCGCACGCAUCCUGCCCGCGGCGCGCGCGCAGGUCGGUGCGUCUGUCGGGGGCGCGCUCGGGUACCUGUACCCCACGUAGUCGCCGGUUACCGAUCGGACUAAGUUCCAGUGGUGAUUUACAAGUCAAGUUAAAAUGUCCCCAGAAGUGGCCUUGAACCGAAUAUCUCCAAUGCUCUCCCCUUUCAUAUCUAGCGUGGUCCGGAAUGGAAAAGUGGGACUGGAUGCUACAAACUGUUUGAGGAUAACUGACUUAAAAUCUGGCUGCACAUCAUUGACUCCUGGGCCCAACUGUGACCGAUUUAAACUGCACAUACCAUAUGCUGGAGAGACAUUAAAGUGGGAUAUCAUUUUCAAUGCCCAAUACCCAGAACUGCCUCCCGAUUUUAUCUUUGGAGAAGAUGCUGAAUUCCUGCCAGACCCCUCAGCUUUGCAGAAUCUUGCCUCCUGGAAUCCUUCAAAUCCUGAAUGUCUCUUACUUGUGGUGAAGGAACUUGUGCAACAAUAUCACCAAUUCCAAUGUAGCCGCCUCCGGGAGAGCUCCCGCCUCAUGUUUGAAUACCAGACAUUACUGGAGGAGCCACAGUAUGGAGAGAACAUGGAAAUUUAUGCUGGGAAAAAAAACAACUGGACUGGUGAAUUUUCAGCUCGUUUCCUUUUGAAGCUGCCCGUAGAUUUCAGCAAUAUCCCCACAUACCUUCUCAAGGAUGUAAAUGAAGACCCUGGAGAAGAUGUGGCCCUCCUCUCUGUUAGUUUUGAGGACACUGAAGCCACCCAGGUGUACCCCAAGCUGUACUUGUCACCUCGAAUUGAGCAUGCACUUGGAGGCUCCUCAGCUCUUCAUAUCCCAGCUUUUCCAGGAGGAGGAUGUCUCAUUGAUUACGUUCCUCAAGUAUGCCACCUGCUCACCAACAAGGUGCAGUACGUGAUUCAAGGGUAUCACAAAAGAAGAGAGUAUAUUGCUGCUUUUCUCAGUCACUUUGGCACAGGUGUCGUGGAAUAUGAUGCAGAAGGCUUUACAAAACUCACUCUGCUGCUGAUGUGGAAAGAUUUUUGUUUUCUUGUACACAUUGACCUGCCUCUGUUUUUCCCUCGAGACCAGCCAACUCUCACAUUUCAGUCCGUUUAUCACUUUACCAACAGUGGACAGCUUUACUCCCAGGCCCAAAAAAAUUAUCCGUACAGCCCCAGAUGGGAUGGAAAUGAAAUGGCCAAAAGAGCAAAUGAAAUGAUAAGCUCCAUUGAAAAGCCUGGCCAUCAAUUACUGCCAAUACAGCCCUCAUCCCAGAGGAAGCCACUCACCAUCCUCUCAGCCUGUGCAGACCAGGCUGCACCAGGCACGGAGUGUUUACAGCCCAGCUCAGUCUCCUGGCUCCCCUGGGGGAGGGGCAGCAGGGGAUGCCAAGGGAGCAGAGAUGCCUGCAGCCCGUGGGAGCAAGUCCUGGCCUUUGCAGUUGCAAAAACUGGCUGCAAGCUGCUCCAGCCCCAGAGGAACUGGCCAAGCUCCAGAGGGCCUCCUUGGAGGGCCUCAGAGGGAGAGAGAACUGCUCAGUAAUUUUGAUCACUUUGGGCUUAUUUCAAAACCUUUGUCCCUCAGUUCCAGGAGGCAGCAUUUGCCAAUGGAAAGCUCUAGGAAACACCAGUCUUGAGAGGUGGCCAGCCAGACUGCCUGUCCACAUGCGUGUCAGCACAUACAGCCGCUUCCUGGAAGCCGCCUGGAAUGUCUUCACGGCAGCGUUUUGCUCACACAGCAGCUUUUGCACGCCCCAGGCAGCCCCGACUGCUGAAAUCCAACUUGAGCUGGCUGGUGGUCCCUGGAUCCUAGAGCCCUUCACUUCGGGUUACUCCCUCUUUCUUGCCUCUAUUUCUUAGUUGGAAGAAAUAAACUCACAAAUUAUGGUGCAGUAAUUUUCCGGGGAAAGUAAAGCCUCAGGAAUGCCCACGCCUUUCUUCCAAAGCCUUUGUCUCUGAGACCUCUUAAGUUCUAAGAUUAAAUGCCCCUCGCUGUUCUUCCUCUGAAA